GUAGGUUAAGGGAGAAGAUGGCGGCGCUAGGGGAACCCGUGCGGCUGGAGAGAGAUAUUUGUAGAGCAAUUGAAUUAUUGGAAAAACUACAAAGGAGUGGAGAAGUACCACCACAGAAACUUCAGGCUUUGCAAAGAGUCCUUCAAAGUGAAUUCUGCAAUGCUGUGAGAGAGGUAUAUGAACAUGUCUAUGAGACUGUGGACAUCAGUAGCAGUCCUGAAGUGAGAGCGAACGCUACUGCAAAGGCUACUGUUGCUGCAUUUGCUGCCAGUGAAGGACAUUCUCAUCCUCGAGUUGUUGAGCUACCAAAAACAGAAGAGGGCCUUGGAUUCAAUAUUAUGGGAGGCAAAGAACAAAACUCUCCAAUCUAUAUAUCCCGAAUAAUUCCAGGUGGAAUUGCUGAUAGACAUGGGGGCCUCAAACGUGGAGAUCAACUCCUCUCUGUUAAUGGAGUGAGUGUUGAAGGAGAACAUCAUGAAAAAGCUGUAGAACUGCUGAAAGCCGCACAAGGAAAGGUUAAAUUAGUGGUACGAUACACACCCAAAGUCUUAGAAGAAAUGGAGUCGCGCUUUGAAAAAAUGAGAUCAGCAAAACGCAGGCAACAGACCUAAUACAUUUCAAAACUUGAUAUUUCAUUUUGCGUUUUAGCUAGAGAAGUUUUCCUUGUGACUUACUAAUGGCUGCAAUGCCAAUGAUUGUAAGAAAACAAACAAAUUUAUCAUGAAAUUCUCCUUGUCAUUUUAUAAAUGCCUAUUUUAACAUCAUUUAUGGUUCCAGAGAUGCAUACACUUUUUUCUGACAAGAAAAAGUAAAAGGUGAUGAGGGCAAUUCUGUCCUACUGUUUUUACAGGCCUUUUUCAAAUGCAGAUUUUGUCAUAAAGUUGUUAUAGAUUUUUUAAAAUGCUUUUUUAAUAUUAAAAUGUACUUUUACAUUCUUAAUCUUUUUUUAGAAAGGAAAAGUUUUCUUCAUUUAGCUGCUGAUUUAAAAGUAAAGUUCUCCAAUUCUUUUUUUUUGCUUACUCUAUUUUUUUUAACCUGUGAAAUUUCUUUACAGUUUUCCAAGAAAUUAAGCAUAACAGUCUCAUCUACGGCAGUUCAUUACACUGUCAAUGUUAACAUCAUUGCUGCAUUUUGUACUUUGAACACACACAUAAUAUAUAUAACCAGUGGUAAAUCAUGACUCAGUACAGUGCAAGUUUUUUCACUUUUACUUAAACAUAAUAUAUAAUGGAUAUUCAUUUAUACUGAUUUAUGAAAGUAAGUUUUUAAACACUGAAACAAUCAUUGCUAAAAUACAUAUUCUUAAUAUUUGAGCAUUGAGGCAAGAGGAUGUAAUUGAUAGCAUUACUUAUUACAUCCCUAUUUAUGUUCAACCGUACAUCAAAUUAUAAAUGCAAAACAGGUUCAGAUUUCAUCUUUUGUGAUUUCUUUUAAAUACUAUUCAUUUUUAUUUAAAUGCACAGUAUUUCCCCUAUAUUUUAGUCCUUCCAUUCCUAGAGACAAACCAGUUAUUUGGUGGUGGGAAGUAGCUGAAGCAAAGAAGGAAAAGUAAUACCUUUAACCUCACUAGCUUCAAGAGUAGACAUUCUUACUAGCUCAAUUUAAAUAAUUGAUUUUAAAUAGGAAGAAAAGAGGAUAUAUUUAAGAUACAUAGAAAUUAUGAUGUGAAGUAUUCAUGAGAAUCUGUAGAUUCCAUCAAAAUAAGUAGGAACUCAUACUAAAAUUGUUGGAUUUAAAGAGGCAACUUUUGUUUAUGAUUCAAAUAUGGGAAUUUGAGAAAUAUUUCAUUUGUCCACUGGAUGUCACUAUUUUACUAAAAGGCAGCUAUUAGUGUGGGACUGUGACUGAGGUCUUAAAGACUGAAAGAGUUGGGGUUCAUUUUCUGUUACAACUUACAGGAACAUUUGUACUUUAAGAAAAAUUUAAGUGACAAAUGUUAGAAGAUGAUGGAUUGAAAAAUAUAAGUAAUUUGGCAUAUUGACCCUAUAUAAAAAAGUGGGCAUUUUGUAACAUUCCUUCAGGAAGAAUAGAAUUGUAUGCUUUUUUCUGCAUGUUUGUGAUCACUGUGAGUCUCAGAUGAUUAUUCCAGUUUUCAAUGAUUUUUCAAAAUAAAAGUCAAUCAGCAUUGUUAUUUAUCAUUAAGGUAUUGAACACUGGAUUGCAUGGUUGAAUGUGUCUUUAAUCCACUACAAAAUGUGCUUGUUAUUGAUAGGAUCAUGUUGUUAAAUUGUAAAUUUUCAAAAUUAAUUGAUGUUUUAAAAAUGUUGAGACCAAAGUAGUAUAGAAGUAUGGACUUAAUUUAAUUGUAAAAUUAUUAGAGGUAUUUGUUGUAGAGCUUUAUAUAUUAAAGAGAGGUAUUGGUGCAUAUAAAAACAGUAAUAUUAUUGUUAUGCUUGUAUUCUUGCAUUUCAGGGUAAGUAAACCCUGAAGAAAUCUUAUUUUAGUAUAGCUACAGCUGCAGUAGCUUUUAAGUAUGUAUCAACAUUUCAUUAUAAAUUAUAGCUUCCUGGUUCUGUGUCUCAGCUGUUUCAGAACUUUCAGCCAAGUUAAAUCUUUUUUGGUGUUGAAACUUUUAGUAAGUUGAGUAAGCUAUUUUUUUCCCUACGGUAAUCCACAAUCUGUUCUUUGUGUGGGUUGACACCUAUUUAUAAUUCUUAAAAUAAGGGUAGCUCAAAGGAGCCAAGUACAGUAGUUUAGCUUGCUACUGUUGAGCAUGAAUAGCAGUAGGUUGUUUUCAUUAAUGCAGUUUUCAUAAUGUAUCCCAGAAUUUUAAAUCUUGACCAUAGAAAAAUACAGUCAUUCAUUGGCAAAGAUGUACAGUGGUGGUUUAGUGCAGUGAGGAAAUGAUGGGAAUUUUUAUCUUAGAAAUGGAUGAUUCGUGAAUAAAACUAGGUACAUAGUAAGUGUAUGAUAGAUGUUUGAUUUGUAAAUUACAAAUAUAAAUUAUCACCCCCAUUUCCAUUUAUUUUCUUGAUAUAUCAAAAUGUGUUGACUUAGUGAUUCUCAAUCUUAGCUACAUAUUAGCCUGGCAGAGCUUUAAAAAAUUGAUACCUGGGUCCUAUUCCAUAACAACUAAAUCAAAAUCACCCUUUUUUUUUUUUUUGUAAAGCUUUCCAGGUGGUUCUAAAGGACACCUAGGGUCAAUAACCCAUUAUAAAAUGAUCUGAUUACACUGGACACUCUUAGGAAGUAUCAAAAUAGAACAGUUCAAUUUGCAGCUACUUAAUGAUUAAUUACAUUUCUUAGGUUUUUUUUUUGUUUUUUUUUUGGUUUGUUUGUUUUUUGUUUUAAAAGAGACAGGAUCUUGCUUUGUCUCCCAGGCUGGAACACAGUGGUGUGAUCAUAGCUCACUGCAGCCUGAAACUCCUUGGCUUCCACCUCAGCCUCCCAAAGCAUUAGGAUUAUAGGCGUGAGCCACUGCACCUGGCCAAGUAAUUUCUUUUAGGAAUAAAAGGUACUUGGCAUUCCUUAUUUGGGAAGUAAUUACAGUCUUAUCUUUUUUUUUCUUUUUUCUUUUUUUUAAUAAAAUCUACCAGUAAUUUAAAUGUGAGCUUUUUAUGUCUGUCAUCAUUCUGCCCCCUUUGCCUUUAAAACUUACAAAAAUACGUGUUUGUUAUUUGAGAAAGCAUGUUUAAAAAUUGCAGAUGAGAAAUAUUGUCGUUAAUAAUUAUGUACUGUCUUAAUGUGGGCACUUCAUUUGUUAGUAUAAUACUAGAUAAUAGCAGCCUAGUUCUUUAGGAUUUGACGAUUCAAAUUUUUUUUUUGUUUUUUGUUUUUGUUUUUUUUUGAGACAGAGUCUUGCUCUGUUGCCCAGGCUGGCGUGCAGUGGUGUGAUCUCGGCUCACUUCAGCCUCCGCCACCUCAAGGCAGUUCAAGCAAUUCUCCUGCCUCAGCCUCCCGAGUAGCUAGGACUACAGGCGUGUGCCACCUCUCCCGGCUAAUUUUUUUGUAUUUUUAGUAGAGACGGGGUUUCACCGUGUUAGCCAGGAUGAUCUCGAUCUCCUGACCUCGUGAUUCGCCCGCCUCGGCCUCCCAAAGUGCUGGAAUUACUGGCGUGAGCCACCAUGCCCAGCCUCAAAUAUGUUUUUAAAAAAUAUCAUUGUCCUCCUCCUCUUAAGAUUUUUUUAAGUUAUUUUGCUCAAGUACUUAAGUAGUCUGGCUCAAGUACUUUGUUUACAAUUAAAAUGGAUAUUAUAGCAUUUAAUAGAAGAAAUGGUUAUGGCUUAUCCAAAAAGAAUGUCAGCAUGACCUGGUGUAGACUUAAAAAACUACAUGUUUGUGAAUAUUUUAUAAUGUGGAAUGAUCAUUGAAAUAUCAAGGAUUCUAGUAAUUGUAUUUCCUGAAUAAAUGUAUGUUUAUGAAUUUUCUAACUUACAUUUUGUUGUGUCCUCUGCCAACAAUCUGGUUUUAUAAUUGUUGUCUAAAGUUUGCUAGUAGUGUUUCUUCAAAGGUUAUUCCAGGUAUGGUUAAGUAGUGAGAAAAAUCACUUAUUAAUUUUCAAGAACUUUGAGACUAAUUUGUAUUGACUCGGUUUUUUAAAAUAACUGGCAAAUGCUAUGCUUCUACUUUUAAAAUUUGUGGUAAUACCCAGAAUGGAUGUAAAAUAACAUUUUUCAAUAGAUUACUUCAUUUAUCAAUUUAAUUCUGAUUUUAAGGCUUAUUUAAAAUAAAUUUGUAUGAGUUAUGUCCUCGUUCUUUGGAUUUGAAAAAAGUUGAUAUAACUACACAAUAGAUAACGUUUAUGAAAGGUAUGUAUAAAAAAACAUAAUUCCUGGUGGCUGCUGAAAUGAAACUUUGAAUUUCUAUAUUUUGCUUUGUCUUUCAUAAAAUUUAAAGAAAACA